AAUUCUGUUAUUGCAACUGCAGACCGUUACCUGGUACGCUGGCUGCUACCUCCCUCACUCUUGUCAGAGUCGGAGCUACAGGCAGUGCCUUCAGCUCUGAGCUCAGGCAUCCCGGUCCCUGUUUUUGCGGUUAAGGACUCUAAAGUGUUGUGUCGUGUUCAUCAACUUUUUCUCAACCUCCCUGGCUCUACCUCUUCUGCCACAAACGUCAGCAUGGUGGUAUCUGCCGACCCUUUGUCCAGCGAGAGGGCAGAGAUGAACAUCCUAGAAAUCAACCAGGAAUUGCGCUCGCAGCUGGCAGAGAGCAAUCAGCAGUUCCGAGACCUCAAAGAGAAAUUCCUUAUAACUCAAGCUACUGCCUACUCCCUGGCCAACCAGCUGAAGAAAUACAAGUGUGAAGAGUACAAAGACAUCAUAGACUCUGUGCUGAGGGAUGAACUGCAGUCCAUGGAGAAGCUGGCAGAGAAGCUCAGGCAAGCUGAGGAGCUCAGGCAGUAUAAAGCCCUGGUUCACUCUCAGGCAAAAGAGCUGACCCAGUUACGGGAGAAGUUACGGGAAGGGAGAGAUGCCUCCCGCUGGCUGAACAAGCAUCUGAAAACCCUCCUCACUCCUGAUGACCCUGACAAGUCCCAGGGUCAGGACCUCCGAGAGCAGCUGGCUGAGGGGCACAGGCUGGCAGAGCACCUUGUUCACAAGCUGAGCCCAGAAAAUGAUGAAGAUGAAGAUGAGGAUGAAGACGACAAAGACGAGGAGGUUGAGAAAGUACAGGAAUCACCUGCCCCCAGGGAGGUGCAGAAGACUGAAGAAAAGGAAGUCCCUCAGGACUCACUGGAGGAAUGUGCUGUCACUUGUUCAAAUAGUCACAACCCUUCUAACUCCAACCAGCCUCACAGGAGCACCAAAAUCACAUUUAAGGAACACGAAGUUGACUCUGCUCUGGUUGUAGAGAGUGAACACCCUCAUGAUGAAGAGGAGGAAGCUCUAAACAUUCCCCCAGAAAAUCAAAAUGACCAUGAGGAGGAGGAGGGGAAAGCGCCAGUGCCCCCCAGACACCAUGACAAGUCCAACUCUUACCGGCAUCGUGAAGUCUCUUUCUUGGCAUUGGAUGAACAGAAAGUUUGCUCCGCUCAGGAUGUUGCCAGGGAUUACUCCAAUCCCAAAUGGGAUGAAACCUCACUUGGCUUCCUCGAAAAGCAAAAUGAUCUUGAAGAGGUGAAAGGACAAGAAACAGUUGCUCCCAGGCUCAGCAGGGGACCGCUGAGAGUGGACAAGCAUGAAAUCCCCCAGGAGUCACUGGAUGGAUGUUGCUUGACUCCUUCCAUCCUUCCUGACCUGACUCCCUCCUACCACCCUUAUUGGAGCACUUUGUACUCUUUUGAAGACAAGCAAGUCAGCUUGGCUCUUGUAGACAAAAUUAAAAAGGAUCAAGAGGAGAUAGAAGACCAAAGCCCACCAUGCCCCAGGCUCAGCCAGGAGCUGCCAGAGGUGAAGGAGCAGGAAGUCCCAGAGGACUCUGUGAAUGAAGUUUACUUGACUCCCUCAGUUCACCAUGACGUGUCUGACUGCCACCAGCCUUAUAGCAGCACCUUGUCCUCAUUGGAGGAUCAGCUUGCCUGCUCUGCUCUGGAUGUAGCCUCCCCCACCGAGGCGGCCUGUCCCCAAGGGACUUGGAGUGGAGACUUGAGCCACCACCAGUCAGAGGUGCAAGUUUCACAGGCACAGCUGGAACCAAGCACCCUGGUGCCCAGUUGUCUGCGACUACAGCUGGAUCAAGGGUUCCACUGUGGGAACGGCUUGGCCCAGCGGGGCCUUUCCUCCACCACCUGCAGCUUCUCAGCCAAUGCUGAUUCUGGGAACCAAUGGCCCUUCCAAGAGCUGGUUUUAGAGCCCUCUCUGGGGAUGAAGAACCCUCCCCAGCUGGAAGAUGAUGCACUUGAAGGCUCAGCAAGCAACACACAAGGGCGUCAAGUCACUGGCCGGAUUCGUGCCUCCCUUGUCCUGAUACUGAAGACCAUCAGAAGAAGACUCCCGUUCAGCAAGUGGAGACUGGCAUUCAGAUUCGCUGGCCCGCAUGCUGAGAGUGCAGAGAUACCAAAUACUGCUGAAAGGAUGCAAAGGAUGAUAGGAUGAAAGAAUGUCACAAAAAGCAGCUUUUCCACUUGAUAAAAACAACUAAAACAGCAAAGCAAGUUUAAGUCCAAACACAAUAUUGCAGGGGUCCUUCACUGAGGAUUGAAUUUCAGACACAGAAUACUCUUGAUGACUUCAAGCCACUAUGCUCCUUUGAUUUGAGAAGCCACAUUCCAUCCCCCUCCAAUUGUGAUCAAUACCUAGGGAGACCAAUGCCCAGAUGGACAAAUAGCAUUGACUGGCAUUAGCCCUGUUUCUCAAUUCCCAUCAUGUAGAGAACAGGAGUCCGCAGCUGCUGGCAGGAGACAGCAUGUCAGCCGGGACUCUGCCAGGGCAGAGUAUGAGCAAUGCCAUGUUCUUGCUGAAAACGUUUAGCCUGAGUUUCAUAGGAGGUAACCCUCAGAUAACUGCAGAAUGUAGAACAUUGAACAGGACAACUGACAUGUCUCCUUCAAACAGUCCAUGUCACCACCAAGAAAACAACAAAAAGGAGAAGAGACAUUUUGAGUUCAAAAAGAGUAAAAAGCCUAUGCAGCUUAUGCUUUUUUAGUCAUUUUGAACCCAAAACAUCUCCUUAUCUUUUUGUUGUUGUCAUCAAUGGUGGUGACAUGGACUUGUUUGUGGAGGACGGGUCAGCUCUCUGGCUCAAUGGUCUACAUUCUGAAGUUAUCUGAAAAUGUCGUCAUGAUUAAAUUCAGCCUAAACAUUUUACCAGGAACUCUGCAGAGUCCAUGCUGUGAGCUUCCUACCUCAGCCCAUCUGCAGGCAGAGAAGGCCCAGUGUGUCCAUCCCCAGUGCGGUGAUACUAGGAUGUUCACUUGGUCAAGGAGGGGUCUAGGAGCUCUGUCCCUUGUAAAGACACCUUAUUUAUAAUUAAAUUGGAAAGUGGUUUGAAAUAGUAUAAAUAUCCUGUAUUCUAACAAUCUUCUUCUGAGUAUUUUAUCAUCAAUUAAUCACCCCUGCCUGUGUCAGUUAUUAUAUUUAUGUUUUUACAUUGGAAAUUGUCUUCUCAAAAUUUUACUAUGUACUUGUUUUUGCUGGCAUUCUGUCGUAAAAAGGAACAUUCCCUGCCCAAAGUUUGACUUUCAUCCAAAAUUAAUUUUAGU